AGUCCCCGCGCCGAGGCUGCGCCGCGAGCUGCCCGCGCCGCGCCCCCCGCGCCGCCCGCCAGCCCCGCUGCGACAUGGCCCGCGCCGCCCGCCGGAGGCCCGCGACCCCGGAGCGCGGCGCGGCCGGCCGCUGAGCGCAGCCUGGAGGCGGGAGGCCCGGCCCGGCCUCGGAGCGAGCGCCCGCGCGGCCUGGCCCCCUCCCUUGCGCUGCUCCCCGCGCUCCGUGCGCCUAGCCGCCGCCGCGGCCCGGCCCAGCCAGAGCAUGGAGACGGCGGAGAAGGAGUGCGGCGCCCUGGGCGGGCUCUUCCAGGCCAUAGUCAACGACAUGAAGCCAAUUUGCAAGGAACUUUGGGAUGAGACAGAAGGAAGUGGGCCCAGAUCAUAGCAAGAGGUUCAAGCCAGACAUCGGGCAUGAUUUGCUGACAUGUGGAGGCAAAACAGGAGAGGCUUCACCUGGGAUGAUGCCAAGGACAGAUUCGCCCCUACCUAUGACACAGAGCUCCUACCCUAUCUGGGAGGACUUCAACUCCAAGGCCACGAAGCUGCAUUCCCAGCUGAGGACCACCGUGCUGGCUGCUGUGGCCUUCCUGGAUGCCUUCCAGAAAGUGGCUGACAUGGCUACCAACACCCGAGGGGCCACGAGGGACAUCGGCUCGGCGCUCACACGCAUGUGCAUGCGCCACCGCAGCAUCGAGACCAAGCUGCGGCAGUUCACCAACGCACUGCUGGAGAGCCUCAUCAACCCGCUGCAGGAGCGCAUCGAGGACUGGAAGAAGGCGGCCAACCAGCUGGACAAGGACCACGCGAAAGAGUACAAACGAGCCCGGCAUGAGAUCAAAAAGAAGUCGUCGGACACGCUGAAGCUGCAGAAGAAGGCGCGCAAAGAGCUACUUGGGAAAGGAGACCUGCAGCCCCAGCUGGACAGUGCCCUGCAGGACGUCAACGACAUGUACCUGCUGCUGGAGGAGACGGAGAAGCAGGCCGUGCGCCGGGCGCUGAUCGAGGAGCGGGGCCGCUUCUGCACCUUCAUCACCUUCCUGCAGCCUGUGGUGAAUGGAGAGCUGACCAUGCUGGGAGAGAUCACCCACCUGCAGGGCAUCAUCGACGACUUGGUGGUGCUGACAGCAGAACCCCACAAACUGCCUCCCGCCAGCGAGCAGGUAAUCAAAGACCUAAAGGGCUCGGACUACAGCUGGUCCUACCAGACCCCACCCUCAUCACCCAGCAGCUCCAGCUCCCGGAAGUCCAGCAUGUGCAGUGCCCCCAGCAGCAGUAGCAGUGCCAAGGGUGGCGGAGCCCCAUGGCCUGGGGGUGCCCAAACAUACUCACCCAGUUCCACCUGUCGCUACCGCAGCCUGGCGCAGCCAGCCACCACCACCGCUCGCCUCUCCAGCGUUUCCUCCCAUGACUCUGGCUUCGUCUCCCAGGACGCCACCUACUCCAAGCCCCCCUCGCCUAUGCCUUCAGACAUCACCAGCCAGUUGUUUAGGAGUGGGGGGCCUCGCAGAACACCUAGUCCAGCCCACUGCCCAGAGCAGAAGUCCUCCAGCUCUGCAUCUUCCGAGGCCUCGGAAACCUGCCAGUCCGUUAGCGAGUGCAGCUCCCCCACCUCGGACUGGUCCAAGGUCGGCUCCCAUGAGCAGCCCUCAGGCGCCACUCUGCAGCGGAGGAAGGACCGAGUGGAGCUCCUGCGAGACACAGAGCCAGGCCCUGCCAGUGGGGGCACCCUGGGCCCCAGCGGGGAAGAGGCACCGCGACCCCGGAUGUCCCCUGCCACCAUCGCAGCCAAGCACGGUGAGGAGGUGUCCCCCGCCGCCAGUGACCUGGCCAUGGUGCUGACGCGGGGCCUGAGCCUGGAGCACCAGAAGAGCAGCCGGGACUCGCUGCAGUACUCCAGCGGCUACAGCACGCAGACCACCACGCCCUCCUGCUCUGAGGACACCAUCCCCUCCCAAGGCUCCGACUACGACUGCUACUCCGUGAAUGGGGAUGCGGACAGCGAGGGCCCGCCCGAGUUUGACAAGUCAUCCACCAUCCCGCGCAACAGCAACAUCGCCCAGAACUACCGCCGCCUGAUCCAGACCAAGCGCCCAGCCUCCACUGCUGGGCUGCCCACCGCGGGGCUGCCCACGGCCACUGGCCUGCCCUCGGGCGCACCCCCCGGCGUGGCCACCAUCCGCCGCACACCCUCCACCAAGCCCACCGUGCGCCGCGCCCUGUCCAGCGCUGGCCCCAUCCCCAUCCGGCCGCCCAUCGUCCCUGUGAAGACGCCCACGGUGCCUGACUCCCCCGGCUACAUGGGGCCCACACGGGCGGGCAGUGAGGAGUGCGUCUUCUAUACCGACGAGACCGCCUCACCCCUGGCACCGGACCUCGCCAAGGCCUCCCCAAAGAGGCUCAGCCUGCCCAACACAGCCUGGGGCAGCCCAUCCCCAGAGGCAGCCGGGUACCCCGGGGCAGGGGCCGAGGACGAGCAGCAGCAGCUGGCGGCCAACCGGCACAGCCUGGUGGAGAAGCUGGGGGAGCUGGUGGCGGGUGCCCACGCACUGGGUGAGGGCCAGUUCCCCUUCCCCACUGCUCUGUCGGCCACCCCCACGGAGGAGACGCCCACCCCACCCCCAGCCGCCACCAGCGACCCCCCGGCCGAAGACAUGCUGGUGGCCAUCCGGCGUGGGGUCCGGCUCCGCAGGACCGUCACCAACGACAGGUCGGCGCCCCGCAUCUUAUGAUGGCGCCACCCUCCCCAUCCUCUCAGGCCCCAGUGCGAGCAGGUGGCCUGGUCUGUGAGCCGCAGGCACUCAGAGCAAAGGCCCAGCCAGGAGAGAGGACAGAGCCAGGGCAGAGGCCAUGCCACUUUAUGGAAAGACACCUCACUUGGAUUCCAGCAUUUAAACAGGAAGUGACUUCUUAGCAAGCCUGGCCAGGACGGAGCCUGCAGGCCUGGGCCUGGUUCGGGGUCUGUUUUAUGCUCUUCGGUCCCUCCUCUUCCUCCUCUGGGGCCCUGCCUCUUCCCUACCCAUAAGCACCAGAGCCAGGGCCGCUGCCCAUGACAGAGGGGCCAGGCUGGCCUCCCUUUCACCAUCCCGGCCUCUCCCAGGGCUGGUCCUGCCUCAGCUCCUCCUGGAAUGCUGGCCCCCCUCUCCCCUGCCUGAGCCCCCUCCUCCCCUCUUGCCUUCUCUCUGCCUCUCCCAGGCCCCUCUCCCUCCAGGAGGCGGGGCGGCUGUGGAGGGGCCAGGUGCACGCUGGGCUGGAUGUCUGCUGGGGGCUGGGGGCCAGGGCGGCAGGUUGGAGUUGGGCGGCCAGGCCCCCCGUGUGGGAAGGGAGUUCCAGGGCCCACGCCAAGUCUCAGGGAGGAAACCAGGGGCUGCUUGGGGGGGGGGGUCUUGGGGGCCCUGUGGUGGCUCCCACCCCUCGCCUCCCCCACCCCGUGAGGCUGGCUGGAGGGGGCCAGAGCAGCUCUUUGGAAACUAGGGCAGCAGGGUUAGGAGGCCGGAGGCCCUGGGGUCACCGGCCAGCCACACAGGCACCGUUUUCAGAUGUCCACUUCUCAUUGGGUACAUCAAUCUUUUAACUUUGGGGGUCACAGUUUUAGCCACCUUUCGGGGGGUGACUGGAGCAGUAGGAGGUGUGGGGUCAUUUUAUGAAUAUAAUAAAAUGGAGCUGACUGUGGACGAGGACUAAGUGUGGGGGAGAGGGGACGAUACAGGGUGUGUGUCUGGGAGUGCCUGGGGGACAGGGACCCCCCGGUGGUCCUAUGGCAGGAUGAGAAGGGAGGGACUUGGCUCCCCCAGAGCCCGGUGGAAGCUACUGUUCUCUCCAGUGUCUCGAGCGUAGCCAAAAUAAGGUUGGGAGGCUCCCGGCCUGUCUGCUGUGGUCUGAGCUGGCUGCAAGCCCAGGUGGGGGAGCGAGUCUGGGAAGAUUGGCUUUGACUCUCUGUUGCCGGAGGAGAUGCCAUCCCAGCACGGCCCCCACUGUAGUCCAGGCUCGUGGUGGCAGCGGGGGCAAGGGGAGGGGCAAGGCUGCCCCCACCCCACGCACCAAGUCACGCCAAGUCUCAGCAGGUAAAAGCACGUGAGCCUAGGGCGAGCGGAGGGAGUCCUGGUGGCCCCGCAGGUCAGGAGGGAAAGCAGGGCUCAGAGGGCAUCGUGGCCCCAGGGCAGGGUCCUACCUGGGGGUCAGGAGCACCUUGGUCUUGAUGAUUGAUUGAUUGAUUGAUAGAAUGGAGCUGGGUCUGAGCCUCCCAGGCUUGAGCUCCUGGGAGUUCUUGUGCGGUGAGCUGGGCAGCUCCUGGGUAGGUCCGGGCACCAAGCAGGCCCUGAUGUGGACAGAGUCCCAUCAGAGGGAGCUGAUGAAGAAUGGUCCCUGUAAGUAAGUCACUAGGUUCAACAACUGCCUGGCCGAGCACUCAGCCCGUGGAGCUCAGGCCAACACCAGAGCCCCGGUUUUAGGGGCCAGGAGAGCAGGUGACCAAUUAUUUGGGGAGUCUUGGGUAGAAUUUCCGCCACACAUUCUCCCCAGGGCUGCAGGGGUCUUCCGAGGCAGGGCGGUGGAGCAGGAUUCAGGAUGUGGUGGGAAUAGAGUGAGGGGCAGUGGGUGGGCAGACCUGGGCGUCAGAGGUCCUGAUGGGAAAGGAGGCAGGGGCUACCCAGAGAGGGGGGCUCGUGUGGCACAGCCCCCACCGACUCCGCCGUCCCCCUCCCCUGUGAGCCCCGGGGGCUGUACAUACUCUACUCCAUCCCCUUGUCCAUCCCUGAGACCACCCCCGCCGCCCUUGCGUCGACUUAGCAACCACCUCAUAGGCCCACCCACCUCGGGAUCCGAGCCAACCAUCCCACAUCACAAACUUUGGUUUGGGGGACUUUACGUUCGUUUAAUUUCUCAUUUUGUACGGAGAAAUAUUCUUUUCAAAAGCGUCUUUUGACUGAAGUAACUUUCCUGGUGCUGUUGUUAACUCGUUCCUUUUUUUAAUUUAUUCCCCCACCCCAGGCAGCCCUCCUGGUUCCUACUCACCCUCCCCCCCUCCCCCACCCUCCGUCCCAUCUGAACCAUUUGUUUCUUUUCUUUCCGUCAGAUUUUGGAAAAAUUCUCCUCUCCUCCCCGCCCCCUCCACACCAUCCUCCCCGAUUUAAAUAUAGUCACUGCUACAAGUAACAGAUGCACUGUGAAGAUUCCAGUAUUAAUAAAGGUGUACUGUAAUUAACA